GAGCAGCUCAGGGCGCCCUUGAAAGUUCUUGGAUCUGCGGGUUAUGGCCGGUCCCUUGCAGGGCGGUGGGGCCCGGGCCCUGGACCUACUCCGGGGCCUGCCGCGUGUGAGCCUGGCCAACUUAAAGCCGAAUCCCGGCUCCAAGAAACCGGAGAGAAGACCAAGAGGUCGGAGAAGAGGUAGAAAAUGUGGCAGAGGCCAUAAAGGAGAAAGGCAAAGAGGAACCCGGCCCCGCUUGGGCUUUGAGGGAGGCCAGACUCCAUUUUACAUCCGAAUCCCAAAAUACGGGUUUAACGAAGGACAUAGUUUCAGACGCCAGUAUAAGCCUUUGAGUCUCAAUAGACUGCAGUAUCUUAUUGAUUUGGGUCGUGUUGAUCCUAGUCAACCUAUUGACUUAACCCAGCUUGUCAAUGGGAGAGGUGUGACCAUCCAGCCACUUAAAAGGGAUUAUGGUGUCCAGCUGGUUGAGGAGGGUGCUGACACCUUUACGGCAAAAGUUAAUAUUGAAGUACAGUUGGCUUCAGAACUAGCUAUUGCUGCCAUUGAAAAAAAUGGUGGUGUUGUUACUACAGCCUUCUAUGAUCCAAGAAGUCUGGACAUUGUAUGCAAACCUGUUCCAUUCUUUCUUCGUGGACAACCCAUUCCAAAAAGAAUGCUUCCACCAGAAGAACUGGUACCAUAUUACACUGAUGCAAAGAACCGUGGGUACCUGGCGGAUCCUGCCAAAUUUCCUGAAGCACGACUUGAACUCGCCAGGAAGUAUGGUUAUAUCUUACCUGAUAUCACUAAAGAUGAACUCUUCAAAAUGCUCUGUACUAGGAAGGAUCCAAGGCAGAUUUUCUUUGGUCUUGCUCCAGGAUGGGUGGUGAAUAUGGCCGAUAAGAAAAUCCUAAAACCUACAGAUGAAAAUCUCCUUAAGUAUUAUACCUCAUGAAUUCCCGUCCAAGGAAGCAGAGUUGUUAAAGAGUACUGGAAUAGGGGCUGAAGGAUCUAUAUUCCCUUAUUGCAUUUUCCUUAUGUAUAAUUUUCCAGAUGGUGAUGUUACUUUUCAGUGUACUCAUAUGUCUCAUUUUCAUCUAAAAUUAAAUGGCAGGAAACAAGGACUGCAUAGAGAAACUGAGUCUGUGUGGGUUCUGUCUCAAAGAUACAAACUCCCUGAUAGUCUAUGGAAGGAAAAUGACAACUAUUUUAGAAUAUUUCUAGUUUGUUUUUUCAGUGAUCUUUUCAUCCAGGCCUUGUUACUGUUACAGAUCAGAAUGAAAUGCACAAGUGGAAUGGGAUUGACCUGUAGGCCUGCUCUGCCGAGAUGAGAGCAGAUGGAAUGAGUUGGUGACCCCUCUUAAUCUGUAGCCUCAGGGAAACACGGCUACCCAAUGCCAAGAUGGUAAACCCUCAACUCGAAGAGUAAGAUCAGGACGUAUGCUUAAGGUGUAAGGCUGAGGAGUAGCUGGUAGGCAGUAUGUUUGCCAGUGACAUUGAAGGUGAGAGAAACAAAAAUUACAAAUGAAUUUAUUUUCUCAAUUCUGUGGUAGAAGUGUUACAGGCAGGCCUUUGUUCUUAGAGCUCCCAAGAUGGUGGUGGCCACUCCCAAGAUGGCAGCAAGCCUUUUGUUCUCUGACCUGGGGUUCUUGGCCUCACGGAUUCCAAAGAAUGGAACCUUGGGCCAUGUGGUCAGUGUUAUAGCUCUAGUAGAAGUCAUGGGUCACGGAAGAGAACUGUGGAACCCAGU